CUUGGGAAGGAGCCCUGCUGGGGCCGUCCAGUCCCCCAGACCUCACAGGCUCAGUCGCGGAUCUGCAGUGUCAUGCCUGGGAGCCCUCGGCCCGCGCCAAGCUGGGUGCUGUUGCUGCGGCUGCUGGCGUUGCUGCGGCCCCCGGGGCUGGGUGAGGCAUGCAGCUGCGCCCCGGCGCACCCUCAGCAGCACAUCUGCCACUCGGCACUUGUGAUUCGGGCCAAAAUCUCCAGUGAGAAGGUAGUUCCGGCCAGUGCAGACCCUGCUGACACUGAAAAAAUGCUCCGGUAUGAAAUCAAACAGAUAAAGAUGUUCAAAGGGUUUGAGAAAGUCAAGGAUGUUCAGUAUAUCUAUACGCCUUUUGACUCUUCCCUCUGUGGUGUGAAACUAGAAGCCAACAGCCAGAAGCAGUAUCUCUUGACUGGUCAGGUCCUCAGUGAUGGAAAAGUCUUCAUCCAUCUGUGCAACUACAUCGAGCCCUGGGAGGACCUGUCCUUGGUGCAGAGGGAAAGUCUGAAUCAUCACUACCAUCUGAACUGUGGCUGCCAAAUCACCACCUGCUACACAGUACCCUGUACCAUCUCGGCCCCUAACGAGUGCCUCUGGACAGACUGGCUGUUGGAACGAAAGCUCUAUGGUUACCAGGCUCAGCAUUAUGUCUGUAUGAAGCAUGUUGACGGCACCUGCAGCUGGUACCGGGGCCACCUGCCUCUCAGGAAGGAGUUUGUUGACAUCGUUCAGCCCUAGUAGGGACCAGUGACCAUCACAUCCCUUCAAGAGUCCUGAAGAUCAAGCCAGUUCUCCUUCCCUGCAGAGCUUUGGCCAUUACCACCUGACCUCUUGCUGCCAGCUAAUAAGAAGUGCCAAGUGGACAGUCUGGCCACUGUCAAGGCAGGGAAGGGGCCAUGACUUUUCUGCCCUGCCCUCAGCCUGUUGCCCCUGCCUCCCAAACCCCAUUAGUCUAGCCUUGUAGCUGUUACUGCAAGUGUUUCUUCUGGCUUAGUCUGUUUUCUAAAGCCAGGACUAUUCCCUUUCCUCCCCAGGAAUAUGUGUUUUCCUUUGUCUUAAUCGAUCUGGUAGGGGAGAAAUGGCGAAUGUCAUACACAUGAGAUGGUAUAUCCUUGCGAUGUACAGUAUCAGAAGGUGGUUUGACAGCAUCAUAAACAGGCUGACUGGCAGGAAUGAAAACAAGAA